CCUUAAGUAGGACUGGUCAGAAUCUUGCAUUAGUCUUAUGCAGGAUGAAUCUGUCAUGGAUAAACUUGAGACUCUUCAAAGCAACAUAACAAACAUACAAGGUCAAGGCUUAAACUCCCACUCUUCAUCUGAUAGUAAAAAGUGUCUUUCACCCAGAUUUUUUUUUUUCAUUUCUUGAUCCAGUUCCCACCUACCUCUUGAGGAGCCAUUGCUUUUCUUUUUUCUGUUUUGAAGUUCUCUCCCAGUUUGUGAUGUUUCUCCUUGUUGCACAUAGCCACUUCCUUUCUUCCUCUGUUAAAAAAGCUCCUCUCCCCAGAAUACUCCCUUGUAGCACCAUGAUUGAAUGACCACUCUUUCUUAAGUGAACUUCUUGAAAACUAGCUUGAAUCCAUCCUCUUCAUUUCCUUACCUCUUAUUUCAGUUUCAGCCUAUUGCUGUCUAGCAUAUGAUAUAUCUGCCAUUCUGCAUGUGAUAUAUCUCAAUGCCUGUCAUCAUUUCCAGCAUUCCACCCUAUAUGUGGCCUAUAUACCGCCAUCUUCUGUCCCAUGCUCUUACUGAAGUCUGCCUAGAUUAGACCAUUUUAAAGUCCAUCACUACAUACUUCUUCCUCUUCUGGUCCUUUAGCUUGAUGGACACACCUGGUUUCAUACUUACUAAUUAUUGCAUUUGGCAACUGUAUUUACUACUUAAACCAUUCUUUCACCCUUACGUGGUUUGGGUUGGCUGUCGCUCUCAGGAGUACCUGGCUAGCUUGGCUGCAUGGUUUCCCUGCCAAAAUAGAUACAGGAAGGGUAGUACCUCCUAGGGGAUGCUAUGCUUUUUGAGAUAAGGCUCCUGGAAAUAGGUGUCAUCCAGUCUGAACCUAUGAGAAAUGGAGAUCGCUUGAGAUUAUUGCCUACUUAAAGAACCUUAGUGAACUGUUCUACUAGGAUUUACUUUUCAGAGCUCCUUGAUGGGGAAAAAAAAAAUUACACAUUCGAGUUCUUCCCUCAGGGAUAAAGUUGAAAAACUUGUCCAUCAGCUUAGCUAGACGUUAGCAACCACAGACAGAAACUUUGUAAUACUUUUUUUUUAAAGUUUUAUAAUAUUCUUAGUUCUCAUAUUAGUUUUUUUUUUUCAUCUUUUCCCAUUUUUUUGUGAUUAUAAAACUUUUUACAUUGGAAUUGUUCUGUUACUGUGUGGAGCAAAAAAUAAGAGGGGAAAUUGUUUAGACCUUUUAUACUAAGUCUUAGUAUAUCCAGAGGGGAGUGUAGGUGGUGGCAGCUUUACAAUGGAAAGGAAACGUGGGGAGUCCCCAGGACCUGCAGUCAAUGAAUAACAGGCUCCCUCCGUGACUGGUAAGAGAGUUUUGGGAGGUGAGUAUAACAUGACUCAUUCAGGUUCUUUCUUGCUCUUUAAUUUCUGUGAUAUUUUGCUGGUCUAUGAAACUGAUAAGCCUUAAUGGUUGCAGUUUAUUCUGACCCAGAGUUUAUUUUCUAGUGAUGCCUUUAUUUUUUUGUUGGGAUGUUGCUGGAUAGUAAAGUAAAACUGAAGAUCCUGGCCUUUCUCAUUGUUCUCCUUCAAGAAAAUGGGAUUUCAGAAAACACUUGUCUUUAGCCUUCUCAUGAAAUUAAUUUCAUAGACCUGUUUCUUGUUUUGAUGGAACCCCUGUAGAGUUACCUAAUAUAAAGGUAUAUUAAGAUUUUCUAGAGAAACAGAACCCAUAGGCUAGAUGAAGAGAUAGAUUUAAGAGGAGAGUUCUUGUAGGUGUUGGCUCACAUGGUUAUAAGGAAGUCCCAUGAUCUGUAGCCUGGAGAACCAGGACAGCUGGUGAUGUGUUUCAGUCUAGGUUCAAAGGUCUGAGAGUCUGAGAAUCAGGUGGACGGGAGGGUGUUAGUCCUGGGCUGGGUCUGAAAGCUUAAGAACUUAAGGCCGGAUGUCUAGGGGCAGGAGACGAGUGUCUCAGCUCUAGCACAGAGCGAAUUUGCCCUGCUGCCUCUUUGUUUAUUCAGGCCCUCAGUGUAUUGGAAGAUGCCCACUUAAAGUAGGCAGUCUACUUAAAGAGGACCAGUCUACUUUGGUCUUCCCCAAAGUGGAUUAGGGAGGAUCAUCUACUUUACUCAGUUAUCAAUUUAAGUGCUAAUCUCUUCUGGAAAUGCCCUCAUAGACACACCCUGAAAUAAUGGUUUACCAGCUAUCUGGGCACCUCUUACUUUACAUUCACAAGUAAUGUUAACCAUCACAACAGAGUAAAAAAACCUGUUGUUGUUGUUAUUGUCUUGCUUUUUUAAAGGAGAGAUUUAUUUCUGCUGCUAGUUUAACUUCCUCCUAAAACUGGUUUGGUAAUAUUCGUGAACUCCCAUGACUAGAGAAACUUCAGGUGUCUGUAGAGCUCUUUGACUUUCAGAACCGUGUUGCAAGUGUCCUUAACUGAUUUGAAAGUUCUAAUAACAACCAACGUUGGAAUGUUGAUCGUGUUCUAGGUGCUGUGCCAAAUGCUCCCCGCAUAACCUCUCACCUGAUUGCUAAAACAGCUUUAUGAGCUCCGUAUUGUCUACAUUUUACAGGAGUGCCAACUGAAGCCUGGACAAGUAAAUUAUCUUCUCAGGUUACACAUAGGCUGCUGGGCCUGGCUUCUGGCCUUCAAUUCUAACUAUUGUUAUUUUCAUGAAAGUGACACCUUAAGUGCUUUCUUUGGUAGUGGUGUUGGGGUAAGCCUUUGUAGAACAGUUGUUACAGAAAACUUGUUUACAUGGAAGCAUUCCUUCAGCGAUGACUGACAGACGGGAAAAGCAAAGUGCAGGUCGACCAUCUCAAAUAUGAAAAUGUGAAAUCCAAAAUGCUCCAAAAUCCAAAACUUCUUGGGAUUGACAUGAUGCUCAUAGGAAAUGCUCUUUGGAGCAUUUUGGAUUUUAGAUUUUUGGGUUCGGGAUGCUCAACCUGUAAGUAUAAUGCAAAUAUUCCAAAUUCUGAAAAAAGGCGAAAUCAGAAACACUUUUGGUCCCAGACAUUUAGAAUGAGGGCUAUGCAACCUGUAACUGAGAAUUUUUACCUAGUGCAUAUUAUGUCCAAGUAACUAACAACUGUUGAAGGAAAGAAUUUUAACAUCCCAUUUUACUCUCAUUAAGUGGUUGUGGAAAUGACCAAUGGCAUUUAUACUUAGGUUUGUAACAUCAUCCAUUUAUUAUACGGUCUUUCUUUGCUUAUCUGCUGCAUUCUUGAGAUUGAAAAUUUUAUCCUGGAAUAAUAAAUGACCCUAUCUCAAACAGCUGCCAUGUUAAGAUGAAUAAGAACAUCAUAGGGGGAGUAGAUGCAUUUUUGGGAGGCCUCCAUCUGAAGUGACAUGAAUUCAUAACACUCUAGUUCUGUCUACAUGUCAUGCUGUUACUAGGUGAGCAGGGAACUGUCAUUCCUACACCUUAUUUAAUAGAGGUGAUCAGAAUGGAGGAUAAAGGGAAAUAGCAUGAGACUGUGAAUGGAAGUGGGGAUUCGCAUUGGUUUUGCUGCCAAGUAGAAUCGUGUCACCUAGCAAAUCACAACAUUUCUGGCCUUCACUUUCCUGACUAGUAAAACGAGGUUUUUGAACUAGGCUGUCUUUACUGAUUCUUUAACUGCUAAAGUUCUAUGAUUUUACAUAUGAAACCAAACCUAACAACAUUGCUAACGUGUAUUUUUCAAAGCCACAGAAGUUACAUGCACAUUUAAUGAAGUUCCAGUGGCUUUAUUAGAAUUGGCUGAUUGUACCAUUAUAUUGCAUUAUAAUAGCAAGGGUGAGGGUUGUUUACUUGUUCGGGGAAGGGGGGCAUUGGGGCUACUUGUACUUAAGCCUCAGGCCUGCCUGCUUCAUGAUCUUUGCUUGCCUUUUCUCACUACUAAUUGCCCCUCACUUACAAGCUGAGACCUGCCCUCUUUCCCCUAGGGCUAAUGCCUGUGUUGGGAUCUUGAGCUGUCUUUUUGUUAACUGAUUCUCUGUGUUUUUUUGUUUUUUUUGUUUUUUUUUUGAGACGAGUCUCGCUGUGUCGCCCAAGCUGGAGCGCAGUGGUGUGAUCUCUGCUCACUGAAACCUCUACCUGCCGGGUUCAAGCAAUUCUCCUGCCUCAGCCUCCUGAGUAGCUGGGAUUACAGGCAUGCACCACCACGCCUGGCUAAUUUUUGUAUUUUUAGUAGAGACGGGGUUUCACCAUGUUGGUCAGGCUGGUCUCAAACUCCUGACCUUGUGAUCCGCCCACCUUGGCCUCCCAAAGUGCUGGGAUUACAGGCGUGAGCCACCGCGCCUGGCCCUCCUUUUUUCUUUUUUGGGACGGUGUGUGGCUCAUUGCUUAGGCUGGAUUGCAGUGGCACAAUCUCGGCUUACUACAACCUCCGCCUUCCUGGUUCAAGUGAUUCUUCUCCCUCAGCUUCCCGAGUAGCUAGGAUUACAGGCGCCCGCCACCAUGCCCUGCUAAUUUUGUAUUUUUAGUAGAGACGAGGUUUCACCAAGUUGGUCUGGCUGGUCUUGAACUCCUGACCUCAGGUGAUCCACCCAACUUGGCCUCCCAAAGUGCUGGGAUUACAGGUGUGAGCCACUGCACCCGGCCAUGUUAACUGGUUUUCUUUUUUUGUCCCUGAGUUCCUGUCUUUAGGAUCUGAACACUUGAUUUUUAUUUAUUUAUUUAUUUUUUGUUUGUGAAACUCGUUUCGCUUUUGUUGCCCAGGCUGUAGUGCAAUGGCAUGAUCUCGGCUCACUGUGCAACCUCUGCCUUCUGGGUUCAAGCAAUUCUCCUGCCCCACCCAGCCUCCUGAGUAUCUGGGAUUACAGGCUCCUGCCAGCACGCCCGGCUAAUUUUUGUAUUUUUUAGUAGAGAUGGGGUUCACCACUUUGGCCUGGCUGGUCUUGAACUCCCGACCCCAGAUGAUCCGCUUGCCUCGGCCUGCCAAAGGGUUGGGAUUACAGCUGUGAGCCACUGUCCCCGGCCUUUUUUUUUUUUUUUUAGAUGGGGUCUUUUUCUAUUGCCCAGGCUGGAGUGAAGUGGUUUGAUCAUAGCUCACUGUAGCCUUGAGCUCCUGGGCUCAAACAAUCCCCCACCUCAGCCUCCCAAAGCGCUGGGAUUAUAGGCAUGAGCUACCACACCCGGCCUGAACACUUGAUCCCUUUUUUUUUUUUUUUUUUUUUUUGAGACAGCAAUGAUGCGAUCUUGGCUCACUGUAACGUACGCCUCAAGUAGCUGGGAUUAUAGGCGCCCGCCACCAUGCCUGGCCAAUUUUUUUGGAUUUUAGUAGAGACAGGGUUUCACCAUGUUGGCCGGGCUGGUCUGGAACUCCUGACCUCAGGUGAUCUUCCCGCCUUGGCUUCCGAAAAUGGGAUUACUGGCGUGAGCCACCGUGCCCGGCCUCACUGGAGCUCUUUUAAUAGGUGAACUCUGGUUGCCCCUUUGCAUGUCUCUUAUUCCUUCCUCUGCUAUAGGAAUAUAGGCUUUUAAACCCCAACUCCGUGAGUAGACCAGCCUGCUUCUCUGAAUUUCUGAGUACCAGGUGAACCUGCAGGGUGUCAUGUCAGAAACAGAGACUUUUUUUUUUUAUAGUGAAGAUGUCCUUGAUGACUGUGUAUACAAAUACACACACAUACACACUUUUUAAAAAAAGUUAAUUUCCAGACUUUAUGGACAGUGUGCAGAUUCUUUAUUAUAUCACAGUGUUAUUUUUCUUGCCUGCAUUUCCCCCCACCUUCUAUGGCUUUGCCUGUAUUACCACAUAUUUAUUACAGAAUCCUUUGACACCAGUGUUCUGGCUGAUUCCCUGUCAACCCUCUGUUGUCUCCCUCUGUUCCCCACCUAACUCUCUCUAAGUGGGCAGGCUUGUUUUUGGUUAUGAUUCGCCCCAAAAGUUAUAAAAGUACAUUUGGAUCAUAGUUGCCUUUGAUGGUUUCUGCGGUAGAACCAGUGGUGCCAGUUAAUUUCUUGAAUGGCUGCCCCCAUAAAUUGGGAGUAAGUAUUGGAAGUGCUUUGUGAGCUUAUCAGGGAAAUGACAGGACUGAAUAAUGAUCUGUCAUGGGCAUGGUAUGGGGGGUGGUGGCACAUGUGCCAUCAUUUGCCAGUGGCCCCGGAAGCCCAACACUCUGUUUAUAUAUGUGUAUUAAUUGUUUCUUUGGUUGUCCAGCAUUGGACUCAUAAUGGCCUUUUGUAUAUAUCAGGGUUCCUCACCGUUUGAAGUAGAGUUUCCAAUACCUACUUUAACAUUGGCUCAGCCACUUAUAUUUACAAAAGGUCUCAAGAUUUCUUACUGGUAGAAUUAUUUAGAUUCUAUACUUAAUAUUAAGCAAUUUCACCCUUGAGUCAUAAUUUCCAAAGUGUGCUCUCCCAGUAUAUUCUAAUAGCGGUUCCCAGGAUUUGGACCACGGACUGUAUUGAGGAAAAAUGCUGGUUGCUAGGUAUUAAGAACUGAUGUAAAUUAGUAAGAAAAGACAGAUGAUCCAUUGAAAAUGUGGUAAAAUAAUAAUAGGUAAUGUUUGCCGAGUGUGCCAGAUCCUGUGGUAAGUGUUUUAAAUGUUGUGUUGGUUGCUUUUCAUAGUUCCCUAAUGAGAUCAUUAUGAUUAUCCCUAAUUUGUGCUUGAGGAAGUGAGGCACAGAAGCUCAUUAAGUUCCCUGAGGUCACCCAUACUUAAGUGAUGGAACCAGGACUUGAGCCGAGUCAGCCCAACUCCAGAGCCUGUCCUCAUAACCAAUGUGUUGUAAAGGUCAAAGGAGAUUUCCGGAUCUUCACAGAAAGGGAACACAAAUUCACAUUGACAGAUAUAAAUUAUUUUGAGGUACCGCUUUUCACUUCUGAGAUUCAAGUGUGACUCUGGCAAGAAGGUGAUGUAUAUACUUACAUUAAUGGAAUAUAUAAUAUCUUUUUUUAAAAAAAUGAUGUUUAACAGCUGUUGGUAUCAUUGCCUAAAUCAAUUAUAUUAUUAGUGUUGCAGAAUGAUGAUACUCUAAUUGUAUCAUUAUUUUUUCAUGUAUUAACUCUGAUACUUUUUUUUUUUUUGAGACGGAGUCUUGCUCUGUCCCCCAGGCUGCAGUGUAGUGGCGUGAUCUCUGUUCACUGCAAGCUCCGCCUCUCGGGUUCACGCCAUUCUCCUGCCUCAGCCUCCUGAGUAGCUGGGACUACAGGUGCCGGCCACCACGCCCGGCUAAUUUUUUUGUAUUUUUAGUAGCGACGGGGUUUCACCGUGUUAGCCAGGAUGAUCUCGAUCUCCUGACCUCGUCAUCCACCCGCCCUGGCCUCCCAAAGUGCUGGGAUUACAGGCGUGAGCCACCACGCCCGGCCUAUAACUUUGAUACUUUUAUAAAAGAAAUUUACUCCUGAUCAAUUACUUUGCUUUCUGGAAGUCACUUUAUCCAGGAAGGCCAAGAUAAGUCCUUGUUUGUUUUCCUUUUUUGUCUAUUUCCAAAAUGGUAGUCCCCCACCUUAUUCAUGGUUUUGCUUUCUGUGGUUUCAGUUAAAUGGAAAAUUCCAGAAAUAAAUAGUUCAUAAGUUUUACUUAUUUAUUUUUUCUAGAGAUGGGGUUUCACCAGAUUGCCCAGGCUGAUCCCAGGCUCCUGGGCCCUGCGAUCCGACUCUCAAUGUGCUGGGAUUAUAGGUGUGCGCCACUGUGCGCAGCCAUAAGUUUUAGAUUGUGUACCAUUCUGAGUAGCGGGAAGAAGUCUUGUGCUGUCCUGCUCCAUCCUGCCUGGAACUUGAAUCAGACCUUUGUCCAAGGUAUCCAUGCUGUCUCUGCUACCUGCCUGUUAGUCACUUAGUAGCUGGCUUGGUUAUUAGAUGGAUGGAUCAUAAGAAGGGUGAAGAGAGUACAAUAGGAUAUUUUGAGAGAGAGAGAAACCACAUUCACAUAAUUUUUAUUACAGUACAUUGUUAUAAUUGUUCUAUUUUGUUAUUUAGUUAUUGUUUUUAAUCUCCUACUGUACCUGAUUUAUACGUUAAACUUUAUUAUAGGUAUGCAUAUACAGGAAAAAGCAGUGUAUGUAGAGUUUGCUACUAUCCACGGUUUUAAGUAUCCACUAGGGGUCUUGGAAGUAUGCCCCACAUAUAAGGGGGGUCUACUGAAAUAAGUUGGUUCUCUUUGUAUAUAGUUUUCACCUUUGACUUCUGUAAAUGUAUUAUUUAGUUAAAAAUAACUAAAAAUAAUCUUUUAAGUUGAAAAUGAAACACACAGAAGAUUUAAUUAGAAUUGAAGAUUUUGACUGUAUAACUUUAGUGUUCUAACAAAAAGAACUAAAAAAAUGUAAAACUCCACUCAGUUUAUAGUAAUUUGUAGUAGUUUUAUUUAGGAUAAUAUGUGUAGUAGUUUUCUUGAUUGUAGGAUAUAGCAUAUGUUACUCAGGAGGUUCUCAAAUUGUUACAGGAAAGAGGUCCCAAUCCAGACCCCAAGAGAGGGUUCAUAGAGCUCGUGCAAGAAAAAAUUUAGGAUGAGUCCGUGGAGUAAAGUGAAAGCAAGUUUAUUAAGAAAGUUAAGAAAUAAAAGAAUGGCUACUCCAUAGACAGAGCAGCCCCAAGGGCUGCUGGUUGCCCAUUUUUAUGGUUAUUUCUUGAUGAUAUGCUAAACAAGGGAUGGAUUAUUCAUGCCUCCCCUUUUUAGACCAUAUAGAGUAACUUCCUCAUGUUGCCAUGGCAUCUGUAAACUGUCAUGGCGCUGGUGGGAGUGUAGCAUUGAGGACUACCAAAGGUUACUCUUAUUUUUUUUUUUUUUCUGAGACAGAGUCUUGCUCUGUCGCCCAGGCUGGAGUGCAGUGGUGCGAUCUCGGCUCACUGCAACCUCCGCCUCCCAGGUUUAAGCAAUUCUCCUGCCUCAGCCUCCUGAGUAGCUGGGAUUACAGGCACCCGCCUCCACGCCCAGCUAAUUUUUUUGUAUUUUUAGUAGAGACGGGGUUUCACCAUGUUGGUCAGGCUGGUCUCGAACCCCUGACCUUGUGAUCCACCCGCCUCGGCCUCCCAAAGUGCUGGGAUUAUAGGUGUGAGCCACCGCGCCUGGCCCACCAGAGUUUACUCUUGUGGCCACCUUGGUUUUGAUGGAUUUUGGCUGGCUUUUUUACUGCAACCUGUUUUAUUAGCGAGGUUUUUUAUGACCUGUAUCUUAUGCCGACCUUUUUUAUCCUAUGACUUAGAAUGCCUAACUGUUUGGGAAUGCAGCCCAAUAGGUCUUAGCCUCAUUUUGCCUAGCUCCUAUUCAAGAUGGACUUGCUCUGGUUCACGUGCCUCUGACAAAAUGAGUACACAUUGACUCCUCCGGGAAGGCUUGUUAAAACAGAUUGCUAGGCCCCACCUUCGGUAAAAAGUCCUAGUGCUUUACCAGACUGGUAACAUAGCCCAAUGCACAAAAAGGUUGGGAGUCUCUGCUUUGGAUCUAAUGCCAGUCUGCAGGUAUUGCCAGGAGAGCAGAGAAACUAUCAAAACAGCACCACAAAGACCCAGUCAUUAUUAUUAUUAUUUUUUGUCUAACAAAAAGAGGUUGGAUGGUACUGUUAUGUUGCAAGGGACACACUCAAGAUACACUUGUAGUCUUAGAUACUGGUUUGGAUAAACCAUCUAUGAAGGAUCUUUUUGAAAGAUCUUUGGAGGUCUUCUUUUAGAAACUUAAUUAUUGCCUGAGUGUUAGAUGAGAUUAAAAAGAUACCGAAAUGGAAAGGUGGAGGCUGGGCACAGUGGCUCAUGCCUGUAAUCCCAGUGCUUUGGGAAGCUGAAUCAGAAGGAUCUCAUGAGGCCAGGAGUUUGGGACCAGCCUGGGCAACAUAGCAAGACCCCAUCUCUACGAAGAAAUACAAAAACUAGCUGUGUGUGGUGGUGUACACUUGUGGUCCCAGCUACUUGAGAGACAGGGAUGGGAGGAUUUCUUGAUCACAGGGAUUGGAGGUUGCAGUGAGCUGUGAUUGUGCCUCUGCACUCCACCUGGGUGACAGAGUGAAACCCUGUCUCUUAAAAAAAGAAAGGUGGAGAUCAACAGCUUAAAAAGCUGGUAACAGUAGUAUCUACAGUGUAAUCUCAUCUUGUGUGUGCAAAAUGCACACUUGUAAAUAUAUGUGGGUGACAGUGUUGGAAAUGAGCUUUAUUAAGGUGUUAAAAUGGUCAUCUCUAGAUGAUGGGGAUAUGCUUUUAUUUUCUUGGUUUGGCUAGUCUUUGUUUUCUAAUUCAUUACAUUGUAUGCCUACUGUUACUGUAAAAUAAAAAUCAUUUAGAAAAAAGCCAUCUUUUCAGUGAGAAUGUCAUUUACCACACUCUUUAAAAGAGAAAUCCACCCAGCUACACCUCCACUGUUUCUUAUGUUAUGUCUCUGUUUCUUAUGUUAUUUUUCUCCAUAGAAAUUUUCAACAGCUAACAUAUUCUGUGUUUUGCUUAUUUAUUUUUUCUUCCACCCACUAGUACAUAAACUCUAUAAGGGCAGGACUCUUUAUUUUGUUCUGUUUUCCCCAUCACCCUGAAUGCUAUCAAGCAUUCAAGUAGGCACUCAGUAAAUCUUUGUAAUUAAAUACAUGAAUGAAAAAUAUCCAAUAUCUAUGUAUAUUGGGUUAUUGAAGGAAAACGGUGAGUUACAGUCAAGUUUAAAAACCAUUGUGCAAACUAUUAAAAGUUCCAACCAGGCCUGGAUUUAUCUAGGCAGUAGGUUUCUGUUGUUUAAGAUCUGUCUAUUUCCAGUAUUCUCUUUUUUUAAUGGAACUAGUCCUAAGGAAAUAGGAGGAGACGAAGCGCUGGUUGGGAUGGACUUUCUCCCUUGAUGUGCUUUUUCGCCUCCGCAUUCCUGCAUUCCCUCCUGAGACACCAAAUGCAAUUUUUCCAGUGCUACUGUGGUGCUGUAACAUGGGCAGUGUAUUGGAAGGAAUAUGUGUAUUAGGAUUUCUUAGCAAUAUUAUUUUCUCUCCCUUGUGCAUUCUAAAGAGCAAGGACCAAAAAUCCCAACCGUGCCUGCUUUUAUGUAGCUAAGAGUAGCUUUAUACAUUUGCAAUUGAUCUGACGAUUGGGAACUCUGAUUAAGUCAAAUGUUAUUCCCCCAACAGAAAGAAAUCCGUUCUUCUCAUAGUUGACCAGUGUGUUAAAGAAAAAAUUAUUCUCAUACUUGUUAAAAUGGUAAGGAAGACUUUGUUUAAGACUGUUGUGAUGGGUUUCAAGACCGUCACAGUAUGGGACAAAGAUUGGGCUCAACUCCAGAUACAACAAGAACAAGUGGAGGUUUAUAGCUGAAGAGGUUGGAGAGUCAGUGGAUGGGAAAUUACUAAGAGGAAGACAUCAAGGGUAGCGAGAUUCUCGCUUAAAGGACCCUGAGGAUUCUUGUUGAAGGCAGUACGGGAUGAUCAGAUAUCACUUGGUGGAUGUUGGAAGAGAGGGGUUUGACCAGAUAUCGUGGGUGGGAGCAUUCUCUCUAAACUGACUUCGGAGGAUUCUUGCUACAACUCUGAAGGGACAGACACUGAAGGCUAAAGUAGAGGCCCCCUUGAGAAGAGGGCUCAAGGGAACCUGACUAAAGGUUUGGUCGAGAGUAUCUUUGCCAAGUAUUAGAAAAAAUUAUACCCAAUUGUUAUAUUUUGAUUUUUGUCAAUAAAAACUUGUGUGAUUAUUUGUAUCCUCUCAUUAUAUAAGUACCUACAUCAUAUUAUGGAUCUUGCCUCUUGGCCUGCAAAGCCCAAAGUAUUUGCCGUCUGGCACCUGGCAAGUUUCUUGACUUCUGCCCUGGAGUUUUAUUACUCUUCUCGUGAAUUUUAACAGCCUUACAUUUAAACAAAGUUUACCAUUGAUAGGAGGACCUUGUGCUCAUUGCUCUCAGAGGGCUGGCUGCAGGCAGAAAGAGCUUAUUUAAUGUGGCACACAUUGUUUUCCAGUUUUUUUCCUGGAUGUUUUCAGCUGGACACCCAGAACGUCUGCCUGCCUGUCUUUUUCUGACCACUUGUUUGCCUUCUCCCUCCCUCCCUUGAUCCAUUCAUGAACUCAGGAACACCCUCACUAUUGGUAUCUCGGUUCUCUGGGGCCAUUUACACCUGACUAGAGGAUCUGCUCACUCCCUGUGCCUGGACUUCCGACCUACAGAGCUGUGAGCUAAUAAACAGGUGUGGAUUUAUGCAGCUCAGUUAGUGGUAACUUGUUACACAGCAAUAGAAAACAAAUACAGAUCUUUGCAAGGUUAUCUCACUUUAAAUGAUUUUCCCCUUCUUUGUCUGCCCUUUAAAUUUCCACUAGUAUUGUUUGUUUUUCUUUUUACAGCAAAGUUCAGAAAUGUUUCCCCAAUCAUCUUACUUUUCAGCAACAUUGAAAUUCUGUAUUCCCUAGGAUUCAGUUACAUAUCCCUCUUGUAGCACUUAACACUUAGUGUACACUUGUGUAAUAUUAGUCUUUGAGGUCUGUUUUUGUAUUUCUGCUCUCACUCCCAGGACACAAUAGUUGCUCAAAUAUAUUCUGAAAUAAUGAGUAAUAGGUCCGACAUCAAGAAUUUUGGCUGAAAAAAAAUCAGAGACUCAGACUCCUAUAAGAACCUCAGGAUGGUCCCAGUAGAAAGCUUUCAAUUAGAUUAAAAUGCCAAAUAAAAUGGCUUUUAUUAUAUUCAUAAAUAUUAAGUGUCCAGUGUUCUUUAUUGAUAUACAGACACCUUAAAAAAUGGGUUGUCUUUUCUCUUGCAGCUAAUGUGUUCAUAAGAUAAGGUGAAGUGUUAUUUAAUAAACAGUUUUUCAUUUUUAGGCAUUUUUGAAAGAUAUCUACUAUGGCAUUAAAAACGCUUCAAUUUUUCUUAACGAAAUGCUAUUUAAUUUCAUGUAAACUUACAGUUUAAUGCUAAGGCAGAAAAAUAGGUUAUUUCCUUUUUAUUUAUGACACUGCUAAAUAAAGAAUUGAAAAUAGAAAAAAAAUCAGGCCUCCUUUAUUUUUUAAAAUGUCAGAUCUUUGAUAAGAAUGCCUGGAAACUUGAAUCUUAUUUAUUGAACCGUUUCAGGAGUUAAGGGUAACCACGAGCCCAGGUUGGAAUCUGUUGUCUCAGUGUAAUUAUUAAUGGCAACUCUUUUUAUCCUCCAGUGUGUUUGAUGAUAAAUUGUAUUGUGACCUUAUAGUAUAUGCUACCUGUUGAUAUGUUUGACUUGCUGUCUCAUUUUGAAUAAUUGUUAACCUUGCAGAGAUUGAAGUUAGAAGUACUAUUGUAGAUGGUUUGGGAAGGCAGAAUAUACUGAACUCUCCCCCAUUCACCAAAUCUGUAGGAAAGAUAUUGAAACCGAGUGAUGGAAAUACCCACAAGUUUUCAUGUCUGUUUGGAAACUUGAAGGAUCAUUUCUCUAUUAUGGAAUUUGGAAAUUUUAGUAGAAUGUGUCCAGCUAUGCAUCUUUUUCAUCAGUUUCCCUGGCUUGUAGUUAGUCUUACAAGUCUCUCUUCAAAUGAAAGAUAUUUCCUUUUCGUUAUUUUUUUUGCUCAUGUACAUAUUUAUAUUUAUACAUUAUGUUUUUGUUGUGGGGAAACAUACAUGUUUAUCAUUUUAACUAUUAGUGUACAAUUUAGUGCCAUUAAAGACAGUUGCCUGUGGUGUAACCAUCAUGAUCUAUACCCAAAAUAUUUUCAUCAUUCCUGAUAUGGUUUGGCUAUAUUCCCACCGAAAUCUCAUCUUUAAGUAUAGCUCCCAUAAUUUUCACGUGUUAUGGGAGGGACCUGGUGGGAGAUAAUUAAAUCAUCAGCUGUUUCCUCCAUAACUGUUCUCAUGGUAGUGAAUAAGUCUCAUGAGAUCUGACGGUUUUAUGAGGGGCUUCCCGUGUUGCUUGGCUCUCAUUCUCUCUUGCCUGCUGCCAUGUAGGAUGUGCCUUUCACCUUCCACCAUGAUUAUGAGGCCUCCCCAGCCAUGUGGAACUGUGAGUCCAUUAAAUCUCUUUUCCUUUAUAAAUUACCCAGUCUCAAAUAUGUCUUUAUCAGCAGCAUGAAAAUGGACUAACACAAUUCCCAACAUAAACUCUGUGCCUGUUAAAUAAUAUCUCCCCAAUUUCUCCCUCCCUCAGUCCCUAUAACCUCUAUUCUACUUUCUAUGGAGGCAUUUCCUUUUAUUUCUUUAAUUAUUGCCACUCUUCUCCUUUUUUUCUCCCAGGGGACUUGUAUUACUUGCAUAUACUGUAGGAGUCUUCAUGAUUUGCUUCCCAGUAGUGGCUUUUGUUUACUGAAUUAAAGUAAAAUUAUGUUUUCCCCAAAUUUUAAAUUUUCUGUGCUGUUAUUGAAUCUUCUUAGGUUGACUCAGGUCUGUCUGCUUUUGUAUUUCUGUACUGUUACUUUCUGUCCCCUCUGAUAGCCCCAUGUCCUUAAAAGCAGACUUCUGGAUUGUUCCCACGUUUUCUUUGGCCUCUAGAUCCCCGAAGUAGCCAUGCUUUUCUCUGCCUCCCAUGGCCCUCUUCACGCUUGCGUUGGGUUAACCCCUUACAGCUCUUGUUAGCCUGUGAAUUGUACGAGGCUCAGGGGUGGUCCCAGCCCCCUGAAGCCUGGUGCUGUAGGCACCAACUGAGCUCAUCUGGGGAGUUAAAUGAUGUCAGAUCUCCACAGCCUAAGAUUUUGUCUGUUGAUUCAGGGGGUGCCAAGGCUUUGACUUUUUUUUUUUUUUAAAGCUUCAUAAAUUAUUUUGAUGUGCAGUCAGAGUUGAGAACCAAUGUUCUGCACCAAGGGUAGGCAAACUCCUGCUGUCUAGGCCUGGCUAGUAAGUAUUUUAGGUGUACAGUUUCCGUUGCAACUACACAACCCUAUACAUGUGAAAGCAGCCAUGAAACAAUUCACAGAUGAGUGAAUGUGGCUGGGUUCCAAUAAAACCUUGUUUAUAAAAGCAGUUUACAGGCUACAGUUUGCUGACCCCUGCUCUAAACAGAUCAGCACCAUUAUCCCUGUCUAUGGAUUCCGGCACUGAAGGUCAGAGCAGGGAUCACUUGUCACUUACGUUUAUACUAGUGUCAGGUAGCAGCAUGGAUUCAGAUCUGGGUACCCUGACAUCCGGCACCCCAACAUCCGGCACCCCAAGCUCUGGCUUCACCCGCCACACUUUUGCCUUUUGCUUCCCAGGCGCCUGGCAGCUGUAAUUCAACAUUCUGUAAAGUGGGUUUGGCGGGCCAUUGUAGUGUUAUCACUUCAGAGAGUUUCUUGGUUAGAUAAAUUGGAGAAAUAUUUAACAACACAAAUUUGAGUAAGCAUCUUCAAUUUAGAAUGGUUUUAUUUGGCAGGUAGUGCUUGCCGAAUGCAUUUGGCCAAAGAGCUUUUUGGAGAGGCUAUGUAUUCAAACUCUUGUCCUGCUCUGUGGCUCUCUUGUUGGUGACAAUGGUGUAGUGUUUCCAACUUUAGAUGAGUGCAGUGUGCCGUCAUCCUGCUUUGUCAUUAGAUACCACUUAUACUGUUAUUUAGACCAAGGGUCACCAACCCCCAGACCUUGGACCGGUACUAGUCCAUGGCCUGUUAGGAAUGGGGGCUGUACAGCAGGAGUUGAGUGGCGGGUGAGCAAGCAUUACUGCCUGAGCUCCACCACCUGUCAGAUCAGCUGAGCGUUAAGAAUUCUCACAGGAGUAUGAACCCUAUUGUGAAUUGCACAUGCGAAGGAGCUAGGUUGCAUGCUCUUUAUGAGAAUCUAAUGCCUUUGAAAUCAUCCCUGUUUCCCCCAUCCAUGGAAAAAUUGUCUUCUGUGAAACCAAUUCCUGGAGCUAAAAAGGUUGAGGACCUCUGAUUUAGAAUAUAUUGUCUCAAUUUAAAUUUUGCUCAUUUAAAAAUACUUAUCUAAACAAUAUCUGUGAAGUUGUAGGUUUGAGUUAUUUUACCAUGUUAGUGAAAACAUGUUAGAGGAAUGUUUAUGAACCCCAGAGGCGUUAACAGUUGGGGGAGACUGGUGUGGUGGAGCAGAUGCUGUUGACCUUUUCAGGAGAGAGCACAAUAGCCCAGCCUGGUUGGUAUUCAACCAGAAGAUGCUGAUAAUGAAAACGUCCACUAUCAGCUUUAUCAUUCUCUAGCUGUGAUGUCCAAUUGCAUGGAUCUUAGAAAGCAGUCAUAGGGCCUGCUUUAAGUGCUUCACCACACAUUCUCAUAUAUAUUUACACAAGCCUUGUAUUGUCUCUUAGAAAGGCCUGGGAUGAUAUACAGAUGAGGCAUUAAGUAACUAAGAGGUUAAGAACUUGUCCAAAGUCAUGAAGCCAAAUCCUGGUGUUAAGAUUCAAAUUCUAGUAUUUUGUAUUCCGGAGUUUGCCUUCUGUGAUUACUAUUAAAUGCUCGGUAAUUAUUGAGGGAGGGCAGAGACUGGAAAAAUGACCCUAAAUACAAAAUAGGUUAGAGUUGCCAGCCAGGGCACUGAACCACAUCCUCACCCCUUGGAGGUUCCCCUGCAUCUGCCUCCCUUUCUUUGAGUUGUUGGAGCAGGAUGAGUAUGGCACUUUAAGAAGGGUUGUGGUCAGGGACAUCUGACUGUUUUACAGAGGACCUGGGACUUUAGAUUUUGGUUGAUGUAUGAGGUUUUCUUGUUUUACGCAGAUACCCUUGUGAUUAAAAGUAAUAAUGGUCAAGCUUUUUCUAUGAGUUGUAGCUUUCCCUGGACGACGGGGAAAAGAUGGGCUAGAAACCAAGCCGUCCAUGAAUCACUUAGCAUCCAGAGAGGACAUGUAAAAGAGGUUGGAGGCUCUACUUUUAGGAAAUGACCCCUUUAUGGCCCCUUAAGUAGAUAUACAGUGAGCUGCGUCUGUUUACUUUUUCUCCUUUCCUUUCAAAAUUCUGUUGAAAAUAAUAGAAGAAGCAUAAAAAUAUGGAAAGAUCCAUAACAGGGCUGCAAAAUGAGAAAGUUGCUCCAGAGACCCCGGAAGCAUUGAGGACGUUGUGGAAUAAAUAAAGCAGAUGGGAUCAGAUUGAUGGCGAAACUCCACAGCAAAGGAAGUAGGAACUUACAACCCAAUAGAGACAGAAGUGGGAAUAACUAGAAAAAUGGAUUUUCUUAACAGCAUCCUGGAUGAUUCCCAAGAACUGAAACCAUAGGGGGUGGCAACAAAAGUGACUAAUGAGAGCGCCUGGCCAGGAAUUAAUAACCUGAAACAGCUGCUCCAGUUCUGCUCUCAGUCUGGCUCUGAGGGGAUAGUGGUCCAGUUUGCUUCUGCAACAAGGCCAUUUAGCUUAGUUUUAAAUAAUCUGGGAGAUUUGCCAAGGCAGAAUAUAGUGGGCGACUGUAUAGCAGGAGGGAGAAGUUGUAGCAGGUGCCAGGUAUCUUUUGUGUCUCCAUCUCCACGGAUAUGAGGUUUCUGAACCUAAAAGUAAAGGCAGUUCAUUACCCAUUAUUUUCAUGUGUGCUAAAGAAAUCCUCUGCAGCAACUAAUAGUGAGCGUUCUAGCCCCACAUUUGUAAAUAUGAGCCAGCAACCAAGAAGGAUCAUCAGACAUUUGAGAAGAAAUCAACAGAAUGAGAGGCCACCAAACCAGUCCCAUGGAACCACUGGGGAAAAGUUAACACAGGAAAAUUCUAAUUCAUAGUCUCAGAUCCAAGAGCAGAGCAACUGAUUAAAGAAAAAAAAAAGCAUCUAAUGGGAAAGGUUGAGCAAAGGAGGAGUUCUUACAAGUUAAGUGUGGGAUUAUAAUGUUAAAAAGCUCUGGUGUGGGCCGGGUAUGGUGGCUCACACCUGUAAUCCUAGCACUUUGGGAGGCCAAGGCGGGUGGAUCACUUGAGGCCAGGAGUUCGAGACCAGCCUGGCCAACAUAACAAAACUGUCAAGUAUGGUGGCCCAUGUCUAUGAUCCUAGCUAUUCAGGAGGCUGAAGCAGGAGAAUUGCUUGAACCCAGGAGGUGGAGGUUUCAGUGAGCCGAGAUGGCACCACUUCACGCCGGCGUGGGUGACAGAGCGAGACCCUGUCUCAAAAAAAAAAGUGCUGGUGUGGGGUCAGUAGGUGGGCUGAAGGGAGAAAUGGAAACAACCAAGGACUUAAGAAAAUUAGUCUUCUGGAAAAUUAAGCAGAGGAUUUAUUCCACAAUUCAAAGCAGAACGUUAUUAAGAUGAGAAUUUUGAAGCAGAAUUAAGAAAUGUGAAGGUUGGAACUAAGAGAUGGAAUAUCUGGCUAAGGAGCAGAUGGAGAAAAAAAAAAGGCAGCCUAAACAAUUCUUUGAUUCAAGGAUGCCAUCAACAGUCAGAUGCUUAUUUCCAAACAACUUUUCAGCGAGGGAGCCAGAGAUCUAAUUAUUCUUAAGAGCUGGUUUCUCUAAACGUGUACAUAUUUUUUUCCCACCCAGUGAAAUGCCACUUCCUUAGCACCUCUGUCACCCCCAGCCUUCUCAUGCUGAAUCACUUAACCAUUUGUAUUCUGCAUGGUAUCAUUUUAGUACAAAGCUGCUUACGCUUUUUUUUUUUUUUUUGGAAACAGGGUCUCACUCUAUCGCCUAGGCUAGAGUGCAGUGGCGUGAUCUCAGCUCACGGCAACCUCCACCCUCAGGGCUCAAGCGAUUCUCUUGCUUCAGCCUUCCUAGUAGCUGGGAUUACAGGCAUGCACCAACACGCCCGGAUAAUUUUUGUAUUCUUAGUAGAGACGGGGUUUCACCAUGUUGGUCAGGCUGGUCUCAAACUCCUGACCUCAAGUGAUCCACCCGCCUUGGCCUCCCAAACUGCUGGGAUUAUAGGCAUGAGCCACUGCACCUGGCCUGCUUACACUUUUUAUUUGAAAAUAAUUUCAAACUUACAUGACUAUUAAAAGAAUAAGAAUAAUGGGUAGAACCUCUGUAUAUUUUUUACCCAGAUUUACCUGAUUUUCCCAUAUUACUAGCAUUUUACCCCUUUAUUUUUUCUUUUUAUAUAUGCAUGGAAAAUAUAUUUAAAAUCAUUUUAGGGUAUAUUGCGUGCAUUGUAAUUGCACAGUUUUUCAUAAAAGUAAUCUUGACUUUUUCUUUAGCAUCUUUAGGUUGUGAUAAUAUAAUUUGGAUGCCUGUGUUAGGUUUUGCAUUUUUUUACUUGGGGUUCAUUUAACAGCUUUAAAAAAAAUGUAAUCAUGCAUCAUUGGAAGUUUAACUGUUUUUCUUAUAAGUUAGCUGGCAGCUUACCAGUUGUGACCUGCUUGAAUGAUAGUUCUCUAUGACACAUGAAUGAAUCCCUCCAGCCUCUCCUCAACUUCAAAUUCUGAGAGAUUUGAUAUUUCUCUGCCUUUAAUUAUGCUGACUGUCGUAGCAUAUGCAAUCUUCUAUUACACAACUGUUUAUUUCAGUGCUGCAUCAUAGUGAAACCUUAAUGUAUAAACAUUAAGCCAUAAUUAAGGAUCCAGACUUAAAAUUCAACCACAGUUUGUGUGUGUGCCAACAAUGACAACCACUGAUAAAUGCUUAACUUCCUCCUUUUUCUAACAGCUGGAAGAUUCUUUUGCUAUCAGUUUUAAGAUGGUUUUAAGUUUAGAAGGUCUAACAUGUAGAAAAAGUAUCUUAGGACACUUUUAUUGCAGUAUGAAGAGAAGGAAGAGUACUAGACAUACUCUGGUAGAAUUUUUGAUUUCCAGAAAGAAUCCCAUAAGACUUAAGCAGGAAUAAGGCUGGGACUGAGAUUUAUAUUUCUGAUCUGUACCACUGCAUGCCAUUAAUUAUAGGUGCUAUGUCAUUAUGUCCUCAGGGAAGAUCUUUGAACAUAGAAACUUAAACCCAGUUUUAUUUUUUACUUCAUUAAUUCAUUGCACAGAUGUUGUGGGACCUUUUCUGUUGGGUCUCCUGGGAAGCACAUGCCAGAGGGAAGCACAUGCCAGAGUGGAGCUAGGAGUUAAAGAUGUUUACUAGGGGGAAUUACUAUGAAAAAUAAAGAGAGAAAACAGAAGCAGGCAUAAGAAGUCUUCAGAUGGGAAUUGCAGGUCUAGCACCUGUGAAAGGAGAGGGGAAGGAAAGGUCUGAGACUGUGUCACAGCUAUGAGGAAGGCUUGGCCAGCCCUUUGCAAAGCUCUGGUAGAGAUUGCCCACCAGAAGUCUGCUGGGUAGAAAUGCAGAGCCCCGCUACCACUGCUGUGCUCAGUCAUUGGCUGGGGACUGCCUGCAAAGUGCAUGACUCUGCUUGAAAAUUGACGGAGGCAGAUCCUCUAGACGUCUGUGGCUGGGGGCCCUCAGCUAACUGCUCUCCUGCCCCAAGGCCCUCUUUUAGAAAGACAGCUGAGUAGGAGCAUGUGGCUGCAACAGUCACUCAUACUUGACACUGCUGGAAUGUUAACUCUGCCAUUUAGUCUGUGUGUGAACCUCAGCAAGUUAGCUAAUUUCUUUUGCCUUGCAAAUUUUUGGUAAUUGUUUUGAAGAAAAUAAUAAUAUCUACAUCAUGGGUUUUGUUUUGUUUUGUUUGAGACAGGGUCUUCCUCUGUGGCCCAGGCUGGAGUGCAGUGGAACUAUCAUAGCUCACUGCAGCCUCAACCCCCUGGGCUUGAGCAAUCCUCUCCACUCAGUCCUCCAAGGAGCCAGGACUACAUGCUCACACUACCAUGCCUGGCUGUUGUCUUUACUUUUUUUUUUUUUUUAAGAGUUGGGGUCUCACUGUGUUGCCCAGGCUGGUCUCUAACUCCUGGGCUCAAGCAGUCCUCCUGCCUCAGCCUCCCAAAUUGCUGGGAUUAUAGGUAUAAGCCACUGAACCCAGCUGUAUCACAGGGUGCUGGUGAAGAAUGAUUGAGUAUAUUCACUGCACAAUAUGAUCACUCAGAUAUUCACCAUUAUGUUCUUUUUUUGUGAGGAUGCAAUUAUGGUCAAAUUGGAAAAGAUUUUUAUACUUUAUGUAUUUUACUUUGUUGUGAGAGAAAUGGUAGAUACACAAAUGCCUGAACAGAGUGAUUUCAAAUAAUGAGAAGUGUUACAACAAGGUGAAUAGAGUGAAGGCAAAACAUUUCUUGACACACAAGAGCUAAAGCAUACCACCCAGAAUUAUUUUCUGCAAAAAUGAAUGAAUGAGUCAAUGCAUCCAAUCAAAGGAAGAGACAUUGAUGAACCAAGUAACUAACCAUGCUUAUGACAAAAUUGAUUUAAUUGCUGAUGCCAUGUGGGAUUAAAUGUAAUUUUAAUAUGAAGAAUUAUCAAAUGGAUGGAGAAUUUUGAGAUUCAGUAGAUACUCUCAUUUUUGCUAGGAAGAAUUAUUUUAGAAAAUGGCGUUUGAUUUGCAUUUAUCUGAAAACAGAAUAAGCUGAGACAGAGUAAAACAGAAGUUGGCAAACUUUUUCUGUAAAAGAUCAAUUAGUAAAUAUUUUAGGUUUUACAGACCAGAAUGUCUGUUGCCACUACUCAACUCUGCUGUCCUAGCACAUCCUCAAUAUUUGGUAACUCUUGGUCCUAUUAAAAUUAUUGUAGGAGGUAUCUUCUGAAAGAGGAAAUCCUUUGUACACGUCUGUUUUACUCUGUAAAACUUUCACAAAAACAUACAAAUAAAAAUAAAAAGCAGCCAUCAACAAUAUGUAAACAAAUGGGCAUGGUUGUUUUCAACAAACCUUUAAGGGCAUUGAAAUUUGAAUUUCAUACAAGUUUCAUGUGUCAUGAGGUAUUGUUCUGAUUGUUUUUCAUGCAUUUAAAAAUUUAAACACUGUUCUUAGAGGUCGUAGGCUUUAAAGAAAACCAGUGGCUGGCUGGGUUUUUUUGCUUUUGAACUAGAACUUUGAAGAAUGUUGGGAGUCACCAGUUUUCAUGACUGGGGUAAAUGAAGGAAAGCACUGAAAAUUUAUUUUUGAGGAGUUAACAUUCCUGAUUUUUGCUUAUCACAGGUGGCUCUAAAACUUUAGGAUGUGUACCAAUUGAAGUUAGUGACUCACCUGGCCCAAAAUCUAGCCAACCUUCCUUUCUUAUCUCUUUUUCUUGUACUUGAUAAACAAUGUUGUAGCAAUAACACAUAUUAUUAUACAGGCCAAAUCUAACACAGUGUCAAUUUACAUUAGUACAAUUUGUAAAAUGGCAAAUCAGAAAUGUCAAGGUGUGGAAAUUUUUAUUGUUUUGAGACUGGGUCUUGCUCUGUCACCCAGGCUGGAGUGCAGUAGCCAGAUCAUAGCUCACUAUAAACUCAAACUCCUGGGCUCAAGCGAUCCUCCUCCUUGGCCUUCCAAAGCACUGGGAUUACAGGCAUACUAGGGCCUCAAAGAGUGGAAAUUUUAAAUAUGUAAAUAUAUGCCUUGAUCUUUCUGUGUGAAUACCUAAAGUGCUUCCUCUCCCUGAGUCCUACAACACUGCAUCUUUCUGGUAUUUCAUUUUGUAGAUAGACAAAAGAAUUCCAUAAAGUCCCCUAUUAUUGGAACCAACGUAAGUAUACAGCAAUUAGCUUUUACAGACAGUAGUGCAAUGAAUAAUUUUGCUGUAUAAGUAUAUAAUUAUAUAAGAUGUAAUAUGUAAUAUAUUUUGUACAAGUGCAAGUAUGUCUUUAGGGUAAAUUUUUAGAAGAGGAAUAAAUGGAUGAAAUAGUGUAUAUAUGUUUAUACUUUUACCCUCCAUAGUUUUGUUUUGAUUUUUUUUGUUUUGUUUGUUUUUAAGUGACCGGGUCUUGCUAUGUAUAUCACCCACGCUGAUAUUGAACUUCUGGGCUCAAGCAAUCCUCCCACCUUCACCUCCUGAGUAGCUGGGACUACGGGAGUUAAGCUACCAUGCCCAGCUGAUUGUACUGAUUUAUAGCAAAAUAUUGAGUGGCUGUGUCCCUCAGAAUAUAAAAUGUGUGAUCACAUUUUUCCCCCACUGUGAAAAGUUAUUUGUGACAUCUCGUUUUAAUUUGUGUUUCCCUCAUGACUAAGGUUGUCGUACAUCCCUUUAUUUGAUUGUGAUCCAUUGGUGUUUAUUUUUCCUGAACUAUCUGUUCAAGCCUUUUGCCGAUUUUUCUUUCUUCUUUGUUUGGCAAAAGAUUUUUAAAUACUUUAAGUGCUGAGAUACAUGUGCAGGACGUGCAGUUUUGUUACAUAGGUAUACAUGUGCCAUGGUGGUUUGCUGCACCCAUCAACCCGUCAUCUACAGUAGGUAUUUCUCCUAAUGCUCUCCCUCCUCUAGCCCUCCACCCCGUGACAGGCCCCUGUGUGUUAUGUUCCCCUCCCUGUGUCCAUGUGUUUUCAUUGUUCAACUCCCACUUAUAAGUGAGAACGUGAGGUAUUUGGUUUUCUGUUCCUGUGUUAGUUUGUUGGGAAUGAUGGUUUCCAGCUUCAUCCAUGUCCCUGCAAAGGACAUGACCUCAUCCUUUUUUAUGGCUGCAUAGUAUUCCAUGGUGUACAUGUGCCACAUUUUCUUAUCCAGUCUAUCAUUGAUGGGCAUUUGGGUUGGUUCCAAGUCUUUGCUGUUGUGAAUAGUGCUGCAGUAAACAUACGUGUGCAUGUGUCUCUAUAGUAGAAUGAUUUAUAAUUCUUUGGGUAUAUACCCAGUAAUGGGAUUGCUGGGUCAAAUGAUAUUUCUGGUUCUAGGUCCUUGAGGAAUCGCCAUGCUGUCUUCUACAAUGGUUGAAGUAAUUUACACUCCCUUCAACAGUGUAAAGGCAUUCCUAUUUCUCCACAUCCUCUCCAGCAUCUGUUGUUUCCUGACUUCUUUUUUUUUUUUUUUAUUUGAGACAGAGUCUCGCUCUGUCGCCCAGGCUGGAGUGCAGUGGCGUGAUCUCGGCUCACUGCAAGCUCCGCCUCCCGGGUUCACGCCAUUCCCCUGCCUCAGCCUCCUGCUUAGCUGGGACUACGGGUGCCCUCCACCACACCUAGCUAAUUUUUUAUAUUUUUAGUAGAGAUGGUGUUUCACUGUGUUAGCCAGGAUGGUCUUCAUCUCCUGACCUCAUGAUCCGCCCGCCUCGGCCUCCCAAAGUGCUGGGAUUACAGGCGUGAGCCACCGUGCCCAGCCCCUGACUUUUUAAUGAUCACCAUUCUAACUGGUGUGAGAUGGUGUCUCAUUGUGGUUUUGAUUUGCAUUUCUCUAAUGACCAUUGAUGAUGAGCUUUUUUUCAUGUGUUUGUGGGCCGCAUCUAUUGGGGAGGUUUUUUGUUUCUUAGUUUUUUUUUAGAGAAUUCUUUGUAUGUUUAGAAAAUUAGUCCUUUGCCUUUAAUAGGAAUUAUAAAUAUUUAUUGUUUAUCUUUUAACAUUGCUUAUGGAUUUAAAAACAAUCAAAAAGAAAUUUUUAAAUGUGCUACAUUUUCAAAUUUCCUAUUUGCUCUUUUCCUUAGUUCUGGGAAAUCCUUAGUUAUUAUGGCUUGUAAAUCUGCUUUUCUUAAACUUCUGUCUCUUUCUGAGGCUCAUCUCUGCCUUCAUCUUCAUAGAGCCUUGAACUCUGUCUUCUCUUCUUUCCUUUUAAGGACACUUGCAUUGGAUUUAGGGCCUACCCUAACUCAGGAUGCUCUCCUCUCUAGAACCUUAACUUAAUUACAACCACAAACACUUUUUUUCUAAACAAGGUCACGUUCACAGUUUCACAUUCACAGGUUCCGGGAGAUGCCUUUCAAACCACUUCAGCCAUUCAACCUGCCACAAUAACCCUAUUUGAUUGUUUAUCUGAUUUUUCCCUACAAUGGUUGAUGCCCCAAAUUAUAGCUCCAACACAUUUGAUCUGAAUAUUUAGUACUCUUGAAAUAUAUUUUUAAAUUUCUCUCAAAAGGAUAAUCAUUUUGUGCCUUCUGAUAUACAAGGUGUGAGUGUUGUCAACAGUUUUCCAUGAUUCACUCCAUUCUGGGACUUGCAAUAGCAAGCAACUGAGAACUUCUAAAACUACUUAAUUUUUAUUUCUUCUGCUCCAUAAACUUUUUGAUUUUUUAAAAAAAUAUGUAUAGUAAGUCUCACUCCUGUUUUUGUAUUCCAGCAUAAGCGAUGUACCAAACUAAAACUUGGUACUGUGUUAAAUGGUAGCAGUAGACAUCAAGGACUUCCUUAAUGGCGUUGAAAUUCAAGAGGCGAGAGCUCCAAGUAGCGUUCCUAAGCAUCGUCCAUAGAUCAUGUGGCGGUAACAUCAUUAGUAUAGAACAGAAAUGGGUGUAUAUAAGCUUUAUGACUUCGCUCAAGUUUUAUAUUUUUCAUUUACUUACCUCCUAGAAAGUUUGAAAUUUCAAAGAUGUCAGCAAAAAUAUUGAUUAUGAAUGGGUUUUAGGUUUAUAAUAAUACAUGAUAUUAUGCAUUUGCUAGUUCCACAGUCCCCUAUUUCAAAAUUGAGUGUAAAAGCUGUCUGCAGAGUAGAUUUAUUCAUACUGAUUCUGUUUUCUUGCACAAAAUCCUUAAACACAUCAAAUAAUGUGUAGACUGAAUACAUUAACUUGAGGUUGUAAACUGUAUUUUUAAGGUUACAGUUAUAACGUUUUAAGUGUGAUGAAAUGUCUUCCUUUUUACUUUCCUCAAUAAAAUCUAUCAUUUCUCGUACUAAAGCUUUUAUGACUGAGGAAAUGACAGUCCUUUGGCCGAAGCAUUCUGGAAUUGCAGAUUCUGAGUAACAAUAAGAUAUCCGAGCUGAAGAAUGGCUCAUUUUCUGGGUUAAGUCUCCUUGAAAGAUUGGACCUCCGAAACAAUCUUAUUAGUAGUAUAGAUCCAGGUGCCUUCUGGGGACUGUCAUCUCUAAAAAGAUUGGAUCUGACAAACAAUCGAAUAGGAUGUCUGAAUGCAGACAUAUUUCGAGGACUCACCAAUCUGGUUCGGCUAAACCUUUCGGGGAAUUUGUUUUCUUCAUUAUCUCAAGGAACUUUUGAUUAUCUUGCGUCAUUACGGUCUUUGGAAUUCCAGACUGAGUAUCUUUUGUGUGACUGUAACAUACUGUGGAUGCAUCGCUGGGUAAAGGAGAAGAACAUCACGGUACGGGAUACCAGGUGUGUUUAUCCUAAGUCACUGCAGGCCCAACCAGUCACAGGCGUGAAGCAGGAGCUGUUGACAUGCGACCCUCCGCUUGAAUUGCCGUCUUUCUACAUGACUCCAUCUCAUCGCCAAGUUGUGUUUGAAGGAGACAGCCUUCCUUUCCAGUGCAUGGCUUCAUAUAUUGAUCAGGACAUGCAAGUGUUGUGGUAUCAGGAUGGGAGAAUAGUUGAAACCGAUGAAUCGCAAGGUAUUUUUGUUGAAAAGAACAUGAUUCACAACUGCUCCUUGAUUGCAAGUGCCCUAACCAUUUCUAAUAUUCAGGCUGGAUCUACUGGAAAUUGGGGCUGUCAUGUCCAGACCAAACGUGGGAAUAAUACGAGGACUGUGGAUAUUGUGGUAUUAGAGAGUUCUGCACAGUACUGUCCUCCAGAGAGGGUGGUAAACAACAAAGGUGACUUCAGAUGGCCCAGAACAUUGGCAGGCAUUACUGCAUAUCUGCAGUGUACGCGGAACACCCAUGGCAGUGGGAUAUAUCCCGGAAACCCACAGGAUGAGAGAAAAGCUUGGCGCAGAUGUGAUAGAGGUGGCUUUUGGGCAGAUGAUGAUUAUUCUCGCUGUCAGUAUGCAAAUGAUGUCACUAGAGUUCUUUAUAUGUUUAAUCAGAUGCCCCUCAAUCUUACCAAUGCCGUGGCAACAGCUCGACAGUUACUGGCUUACACUGUGGAAGCAGCCAACUUUUCUGACAAAAUGGAUGUUAUAUUUGUGGCAGAAAUGAUUGAAAAAUUUGGAAGAUUUACCAAGGAGGAAAAAUCAAAAGAGCUAGGUGACGUGAUGGUUGACAUUGCAAGUAACAUCAUGUUGGCUGAUGAACGUGUCCUGUGGCUGGCGCAGAGGGAAGCUAAAGCCUGCAGUAGGAUUGUGCAGUGUCUUCAGCGCAUUGCUACCUACCGGCUAGCCGGUGGAGCUCACGUUUAUUCAACAUAUUCACCCAAUAUUGCUCUGGAAGCUUAUGUCAUCAAGUCUACUGGCUUCACGGGGAUGACCUGUACCGUGUUCCAGAAAGUGGCAGCCUCUGAUCGUACAGGACUUUCGGAUUAUGGGAGGCGGGAUCCAGAGGGAAACCUGGAUAAGCAGCUGAGCUUUAAGUGCAAUGUUUCAAAUACAUUUUCGAGUCUGGCACUAAAGAAUACUAUUGUGGAGGCUUCUAUUCAGCUUCCUCCUUCCCUUUUCUCACCAAAGCAAAAAAGAGAACUCAGACCAACUGAUGACUCUCUUUACAAGCUUCAACUCAUUGCAUUCCGCAAUGGAAAGCUUUUUCCAGCCACUGGAAAUUCAACAAAUUUGGCUGAUGAUGGAAAACGACGUACUGUGGUUACCCCUGUGAUUCUCACCAAAAUAGAUGGUGUGAAUGUAGAUACCCACCACAUCCCUGUUAAUGUGACACUGCGUCGAAUUGCACAUGGAGCAGAUGCUGUUGCAGCCCGGUGGGAUUUCGAUUUGCUGAACGGACAAGGAGGCUGGAAGUCAGAUGGGUGCCAUAUACUCUAUUCAGAUGAAAAUAUCACUACGAUUCAGUGCUACUCCCUUAGUAACUAUGCAGUUUUAAUGGAUUUGACGGGAUCUGAACUAUACACCCAGGCGGCCAGCCUCCUGCAUCCUGUGGUUUAUACUACCGCUAUCAUUCUCCUCUUAUGUCUCUUAGCCGUCAUUGUCAGUUACAUAUACCAUCACAGUUUGAUUAGAAUCAGCCUCAAGAGCUGGCACAUGCUUGUGAACUUGUGCUUUCAUAUUUUCCUAACCUGUGUGGUCUUUGUGGGAGGAAUAACCCAGACUAGGAAUGCCAGCAUCUGCCAAGCAGUUGGGAUAAUUCUUCACUAUUCCACCCUUGCCACAGUACUAUGGGUAGGAGUGACAGCUCGAAAUAUCUACAAACAAGUCACUAAAAAAGCUAAAAGAUGCCAGGAUCCUGAUGAACCACCACCUCCACCAAGACCAAUGCUCAGAUUUUACCUGAUUGGUGGUGGUAUCCCCAUCAUUGUUUGCGGCAUAACUGCAGCAGCGAACAUUAAGAAUUACGGCAGUCGGCCAAACGCACCCUAUUGCUGGAUGGCAUGGGAACCCUCCUUGGGAGCCUUCUAUGGGCCAGCCAGCUUCAUCACUUUUGUAAACUGCAUGUACUUUCUGAGCAUAUUUAUUCAGUUGAAAAGACACCCUGAGCGCAAAUAUGAGCUUAAGGAGCCCACGGAGGAGCAACAGAGAUUGGCAGCCAAUGAAAAUGGCGAAAUAAAUCAUCAGGAUUCAAUGUCUUUGUCUCUGAUUUCUACAUCAGCCUUGGAAAAUGAGCACACUUUUCAUUCUCAGCUCUUGGGGGCCAGCCUUACUUUGCUCUUAUAUGUUGCACUGUGGAUGUUUGGGGCUUUGGCUGUUUCUUUGUAUUACCCUUUGGACUUGGUUUUUAGCUUCGUUUUUGGAGCCACAAGUUUAAGCUUCAGUGCGUUCUUCGUGGUCCACCAUUGUGUUAAUAGGGAGGAUGUUAGACUUGCGUGGAUCAUGACUUGCUGCCCAGGACGGAGCUCGUAUUCAGUGCAAGUCAACGUCCAGCCCCCCAACUCUAAUGGGACGAAUGGAGAGGCACCCAAAUGCCCCAAUAGCAGUGCGGAGUCUUCAUGCACAAACAAAAGUGCUUCAAGCUUCAAAAAUUCCUCCCAGGGCUGCAAAUUAACAAACUUGCAGGCGGCUGCAGCUCAGUGCCAUGCCAAUUCUUUACCUUUGAACUCCACCCCUCAGCUUGAUAAUAGUCUGACAGAACAUUCAAUGGACAAUGAUAUUAAAAUGCACGUGGCGCCUUUAGAAGUUCAGUUUCGAACAAAUGUGCACUCAAGCCGCCACCAUAAAAACAGAAGUAAAGGACACCGGGCAAGCCGACUCACAGUCCUGAGAGAAUAUGCCUACGAUGUCCCAACGAGCGUGGAAGGAAGCGUGCAGAACGGCUUACCUAAAAGCCGGCUGGGCAAUAACGAAGGACACUCGAGGAGCCGAAGAGCUUAUUUAGCCUACAGAGAGAGACAGUACAACCCACCCCAGCAAGACAGCAGCGAUGCUUGUAGCACACUUCCCAAAAGUAGCAGAAAUUUUGAAAAGCCAGUUUCAACCACUAGUAAAAAAGAUGCGUUAAGGAAGCCAGCUGUGGUUGAACUUGAAAAUCAGCAAAAAUCUUAUGGCCUCAACUUGGCCAUUCAGAAUGGACCAAUUAAAAGCAAUGGGCAGGAGGGACCCUUGCUCGGUACCGAUAGCACUGGCAAUGUUAGGACUGGAUUAUGGAAACACGAAACUACUGUGUAACAUUGCUGGGCUUCCUAGGCAGAAAUUCAUAUAAACUGUGAUACUCACAUUCCUUGAAGCUAUGAGCAUUUAAAAACUGUUUACAGCCACCAUAGGGAUUCAAAAGAAUUUGGAAUAAACUUUGAAGUUUUGGAUUUUACUUAUUUUUAUCCCCAAAUUGUUGCUAUUUUUUAGGAUCUGAAACAAAAUCUUUCUAAAACAUUGUUUUAGUUGUCAAAGCACCAACAGGACAUUUUGGGAUGUGAAAUGUAAUUUCUUGGAAUCUGUAAUUUGUACUUAAUAUUUCAGGCUUGUAUUUAAUAUAAUAAAUAGGUGUUUGUUAUUGUGUC